CUUCCUCGGAACUGUUGCCCACAUGCAGCCCCGGACACAGCCCCUAGCCCAAACCCUACCCUUCUUCCUCGGAGGGGCCCCUCGAGACACUGGGCUGCGGGUGCCUGUCAUUAAGAUGGGCACAGGGUGGGAGGGCUUCCAGCGGACCCUGAAGGAAGUCGCCUACAUCCUCCUCUGCUGCUGGUGUAUCAAGGAACUGCUGGAUUAAUGGUAGCAGGGAACUGCCUCCUCUCCCCACCAGCACCAUGGCUGGCAUCGCUCAGGUGGGCAGGGUAGAGUAAACAGGAGGCAUAGCUGCAGCUUCUGUGGCAGAGCUUGCCUUAGCUUCUCAUUCUCUUCUUUAGCCCCCAGCCCAAUUGCCAUCAAGACUCCUGAAGCCAGCUGUGCUUGACCAAGGAUGGGCCAUAAACAAUGAGUAAACAGUAAAGUGUGGAUCCUGCUUUGAGCUGUGUCAUCUAGCAGACCUGCCUCAUCUCUGAGCCUCCUUCAUUCCCAACCCCUGCCUCUGGUGGACCUCUGGUGGGCAGGAGCUUGGACUGCUCUGGCUAGGACCCCAGUAAGAUUGUGGCAAGACCUGGCACUCCUCCAAGCUUGGCACAGUGAGCCCACCAGCUCAGAUGGUUGAUCUUACCAUACCCUCAUAGUACCAAGAAUGGACUGCCCCCUAAGAAACCUGUUUGAGAAUCACUGAAUUAUAAAUAUAAUCCAUAGGCCUUGAGGCCCAAGAUUA